GGCUGGGAAGGGCGCUGAAGAAACAACGCCCAGGACCAGGACUAUCCCCUGCUCAAGCUGUGAUUCCGAGACCCCUGCCACCACUACUGCAUUCACGGGGAUCCCAGGCUAGUGGGACUCGACAUGGGUAGCCCCCAGGGCAGCUCCCUACAGCUUGGGCCAUCUGCACUUUUCCCAAGGCCCUAAGUCUCCGCCUCUGGGCUCGUUAAGGUUUGGGGUGGGAGCUGUGCUGUGGGAAGCAACCCGGACUACACUUGGCAAGCAUGGCGCUACUGAAAGUCAAGUUUGACCAGAAGAAGCGGGUCAAGUUGGCCCAAGGGCUCUGGCUCAUGAACUGGUUCUCCGUGUUGGCUGGCAUCAUCAUCUUCAGCCUAGGACUGUUCCUGAAGAUUGAACUCCGAAAGAGGAGCGAUGUGAUGAAUAAUUCUGAGAGCCAUUUUGUGCCCAACUCAUUGAUAGGGAUGGGGGUGCUAUCCUGUGUCUUCAACUCGCUGGCUGGGAAGAUCUGCUACGACGCCCUGGACCCAGCCAAGUAUGCCAGAUGGAAGCCCUGGCUGAAGCCGUACCUGGCUAUCUGUGUUCUCUUCAACAUCAUCCUCUUCCUUGUGGCUCUCUGCUGCUUUCUGCUUCGGGGCUCGCUGGAGAACACCCUGGGCCAAGGGCUCAAGAACGGCAUGAAGUACUACCGGGACACAGACACCCCUGGCAGGUGUUUCAUGAAGAAGACCAUCGACAUGCUGCAGAUCGAGUUCAAAUGCUGCGGCAACAACGGUUUUCGGGACUGGUUUGAGAUUCAGUGGAUCAGCAAUCGCUACCUGGACUUUUCCUCCAAAGAAGUCAAAGAUCGAAUCAAGAGCAACGUGGAUGGGCGGUACCUGGUGGACGGCGUCCCUUUCAGCUGCUGCAAUCCUAGCUCGCCACGGCCCUGCAUCCAGUAUCAGAUCACCAACAACUCAGCACACUACAGUUACGACCACCAGACGGAGGAGCUCAACCUGUGGGUGCGUGGCUGCAGGGCUGCCCUGCUGAGCUACUACAGCAGCCUCAUGAACUCCAUGGGUGUCGUCACGCUCCUCAUUUGGCUCUUCGAGGUGACCAUUACAAUUGGGCUGCGCUACCUACAGACGUCGCUGGAUGGUGUGUCCAACCCCGAGGAAUCUGAGAGCGAGAGCCAGGGCUGGCUGCUGGAGAGGAGCGUGCCGGAGACCUGGAAGGCCUUUCUGGAGAGUGUGAAGAAGCUGGGCAAGGGCAACCAGGUGGAAGCCGAGGGCGCAGACGCAGGCCAGGCCCCAGAGGCUGGCUGAGGGCCCUGGGGCCCCUCCCCUCCCGAACACUGAGAAAUAGUGCACUCCAAGAAACGUGGAUCUCCCCCUCAUCCAACUCCGAAAGUCUGAAUCUCCCAAGGAGGGCACCAUCUUACAGAGACUCUCCCUGACGGUGGAAUUUAAGUUUAGGGUCCCUAAAAGCAUUUGACACACAGUUGUUGAAUGACUGACCCAAAAUGUGAAUGAAGCUAAUGUGAAUGUGAGUGAAGCUCCCUUCAGGCCCGCUGCCCUAGGAUAUGCCCUCCUGGUGACUCGGGGGCUGUCUCAGACGACUAGCCCAGGACCCAUCUUUCUCACACGGAUUUAGUCCCACCCUAUGGCCACUGGCCGUAUCUGAGGGCUGCUCCCCUUUUAGAAUUUACCUCUUAUGAGCUCCAUGUUGCUUCACUCUAUCCAAAGUGUCACUUGGUGCAUAAGCACAGAAAUCUGAAAAAUGGCCAUGUUGUCUUUUUUUUUUUUUUUUAAUGCCAAGAUUGACAGGUUGGCCGUUUGCUUAAUGCCAGAAGUUGGGGGAAAGUUACGCUUUUCUAAGAAUAAUGGACUCUUAAGGCAUUGAGGGCUCUAAACAGGAUUCUUUAAUCAUGGAGCAAGAGAAUUUCAAGGCAGGGGAUUUUAUCCCCCACCAAAAACACAGUGAAAGGCCUGCUUUUGUGUCCCAUUCACAUGCCCUCGGUCACUGAGUCUGGAGUGAACCACGGGUUGAGGAAGUCAGGCUGUUGGCGUGUCCCAGCACCACACCACCCCUAAAGUGCCAGGUGAUCUCCUGUGGCUCAUCGGUGGAAGCAGUGGGGUAGGCUGCUGCCCUGCUGUGGAAGAGGAGCAACAAUCAGACAUGAGUCCACCCUUUGGAGACCAGGCCUCAGCUCUUGGUGGGCCCAGGGACACCCACACAGGUGGCCAUCACAGCCCCAUGGACAACACUAAUUGUCCACAGCAAAGGGCAAGGAAUCCUCUGGGAGCUUCUUCCGUUUCUUCCCCCCAGAUACCCAUCUUGAAAAACACUAUUUCUGGAAUGCUUCUGCAUCAAAGGAGAUUCUUUGAGAUAGCCCAUCUUCCUGAGCUAGCAAAUACAGGAGUUUUCACUUUCUUUAGGAAAGAGAAGCUUUCAGGGGAAGGAGAGAAUGAUUUUGCUGACUUCCCAAGCCCUGGUGACCAGACCAAGGCAGGGCCCAGCAUAAUUCCUCCAGUUGGAUGAACAUUCAAGAGAGCUCGUUCCUACCUGGCUGGAGACCGAGGCCAGAAGGCAAAAACCAGAAAGGGAACAGUCCAUAACUUACCUCUGCUUCUGACCGAUGGUGUUUGGGAAUAGGUUACUUUGGACUGAGUUUGGGUUCUCUGCUGUCCUAAGAACUUCAGUGUAGAGAAAAUAAGACUUCUGGUGCUGCUGGGGUAUGUUCUGGGCUUAAUUCCCCCAAGCAGAAGACCAGAUCCAAGAUGUUUGGACACCCUGUCAGACGUUGGUCCCAAGUUUAAUUAGAUUUCUGAAUCUCGUUGAGGCCAAGGAAUGAUCCAUACUGAAAAAAUGCUGAGCCAGCCAUCUUUGGCAAAGGUCCCUGAGCUCUUGCUAUCUCUCAAGAGUGCUGAGAACCACGGUGAAAGUGCUGCUCUAGGCCCACAAGUGUAACUAUGCUGUUAACAGCUGUCAAUAGAUAAUUAAAAUUCAUACUGUAUGAAAA